CCUUAGGUGACUUCACAGGGUAGUGAUGACCUCACAAGCUUCCAAAGUUUCCAUGGCAGCGUGACUACACACCUGCGUCCUAGAGAAGCCUCCCUACCAUUUCUCUGUAAGAUACCAAUCUGUUUGGUUGGCUGAGAGAGAAUGACUGACCGGAUCCUCUAUAUUGUCUCUAACAUGUCCUCUGUCCCCUGGGAGGGCAGCGCAGCAGCUGCAGUGCCUGCCACUUCUCCUCCCACACCUGGGCACUACCAUGUUCUCUACCGAGGGUGUGGAGAAACUCAGGUAGGCUGGCAUGGGGAGACGUACUGCCUGGUUGGUGGCUACCGGGUCCAUGGGGAUGCUCCUUUGGCCACCCCAACAAAGGCUGAAGCAGAGAAGCCAGCCCCCAGGCGUGCUCCCAAGAGACGUCAAGCUACGAUAGAGUCAGAUAAAGACCUGGGUUGCUCUAGCCCCAAAAUUCGGCGCUUGGAGCAUCGUGGCAGGAGACUGACCCCACAGAAGCUUGCUGGCUGAGCCAUUUGGGAGAAAGGACAAAUGUUUAGCUGUCUAAGACAGCUAAUGCCUCUUCUGCGGUGACCUCCCCUGCCCACCACUGCAGAUAGAGCCUGAGUCAUUCUGCCUAUGCCUUCCUCAUCCAGAAGCCCCCUUCCAUGCUAACUACCCAUGGCCAAGGAGCCUCAGAAACUGUGGUUUAAAAUGAGAGGUUGCUUUGAACAUCCCAAGGCUGAAGACGGCCUGGAAGAAAACCUGAUGUUCCUCUACUCAUCUCUCCAGAGUCCCUUUUUGGGCAGAAGAUAGAAAUAGUCUGCACUCUGCUAGCCGAGGAGUCAAGUGCAGAGAGGGAGUGCAGCAUAGCCCAGUAAGGGCUUGAUCUACCAGAUGGGUCUUUGCUUUGAGUCACUGCCAGCAACUACCAGCACAAACCAGGAGGGCCAGGACUUGCUGAAACUGGAAGCAGCAGCCCAUGGCUAGUCACAGCAGGAGAAAGCCUCCUGCUUGGCAUCUCAGGAGGUAGAAGAAAGAGACCUGGGGAGACCUGCCACCUACAGCAAGAACAAUAAGGAGGAAGUUGAGCAACAUCCCCCUGAAGCUCACAUGUUACUUUAUUUCCUGCCCAUUAUGGCCCCAGUGAGGUCCCUACUGCUCAAUUUAAAAAAAAAUUAAAAAAAUUAUUUUUCCAUAACA